GGGCAGAAAUAUUUCAUAGAUGAUUAUGCAGCAAAGUUAAACUCACAUUUGCAACCAUGCAAAUAAAGAUAUAUUCUCUUUCAUUGUUUUGUACUUUUUUGCCUUGUCUGAGCAUAGAAAAUUAGAUUCAACCAGCUUGAGUUCUGAGGUACAAAUAUUAUAAAAAUCUGAUUCAUAGAAUAUGUAGCUAAAUGAAGCUUUUAUGGCUAAUAGCAUAGCCAAUGAAGCUUUAUAAAAUAUGCAAAGACUUACCUAUGCUAUUUCAAAAGAGUGCUCAAUUUCUUGUGGAGCUAAAGCUGGAUCUGGUCAAUACUGUGACUAAAGAGAAACUCGUUUACAAAGCAUCCAUCUUUCUCAUUCCCUGCCUCAUCACUACUUAGCAGUGCUCACCACCAUCCCUCCAUAGGCACCAAAUGCCUUCACAUUUUAUCCGCUUUUCCCCUCAUAUUUCUUUUUUAAACUUAAAAGUGAUAAAAAAACAAAUUUUACAAAAUCAGCAACAGCUACCAAAGAAAGCAGUACUAUAUUACAUCAUAACUUGCAAAACUGAAAACCAAGCAAAGAAAUAGAUACACUAGUUCCCCUUAUCCAUGAGGCCUAUGUCCCAAGACCCCCAGUGGAUGCCUAAAACAGCAGAUAGUACCAAACUCUAUAUACAAUAUAUUUUUUUCCUGUAUUCACCUACCUAUGAUAAAGUUUAAUUUGUAAAUCAAGCACAGUAAAAGAUUACAAAAAUAACUAAUAAUAAAAUAGAACAAUUAAAACAAUAUACUAUAAUAAAAGUUGCCAGGGGUUGUGGCUCAUCCCUGUAAUCCUAGCAAUUUGGGAGAUUGAGGCGGGAGGACCGCUCGAGCCCAAAAGUUUGAGACCGGCCUGGGCAACAUAGGGAGACCCUGUAUCUAAAAUAAAUAAAAAUUAAAAAAAUAAAAAGUAAAAAAAUGUGUUAAAAUAUAUAGUGUGGUGUCUCUCACUCUCUCAAGAUACCUUACUGUACUGUACACACCUAUUUUUGGACUGUGGUUGACCUUGGGUCACUGAAACUGCAGAUAAGCGGGGACUAAUGUGUUCAUUGUGAAGAGUCAAGGUUCCUCACCCCGCCCCACUCUUUCAAAAACUACCGAAAAAAAGUGGAUUACCAAAAUUCUGAAAACGUGGAGACUCAAGAAAGAUUGUCUAAUUCAAAAUUAAUAUAAAUAAAACACUUUAUCUUGAUUAUAAGAUAAUAAGUAGCCAUUUAGCUAGAUGAAUACAAAGCUAUUUUUAUUUAAUAAAGAUAUAAUUUGUGAAUUAUGAAUGUUUGUAUUUUAUUACUCAUGCAAUCUUUAUUGGGUGAUCUACAGAGUACUAAAAAAUUUACAAAAUAAUUGCAUCAUCUUUAAUGAUUUGCAAGUUUCAAUUAUAACUUAAAAUAGGUAGAUAUUUUCUAUUUUGUUGUUAUAAUGGUAUAUUUGUCAAGAUAGAAUAGAAAAUGUCUCCUUUAACAGUUUGUUAGGUUUGUAUAUUUAUGACCUUUAAAUAUGUAGCUAUGUGGCAUGUGGUCUUCCAUUUGCAUUCUUGACCCAGGGCUGAAGAGAUCUUUUAUACUUUUUCAUUUUAGGGUGUUCUUCCUACCUAUCUAGAGAAAAGGGUUUGGGGAUGCCGGUCACAACUUGAUAAUACCCCAAAUCUGUACAAAUAGGCCUGAGGAAUGGUACUGUACUUGCUGGUAUAUGAAAAAAUACCACAGUUUUUAGAACUUGUGAUAUAACACAUGACAAAGACAUAGAGAAUGGAUAACAGGCUUGCGGUUCUGAGCUGCAUUUUCCUGGUGUGUUUCCAUAAGAGAAAACAUUUAAAAAUAUAAAUUUAAUCAAAGAGAUGUAGUCUCUCACUUCUAUAAGAGAAAGAGAAUAGAUGCUAGGGAGCAUCACAGAAAAACUUUUUCAGCAGUCUGAACUGAAAAGGAAAAUGAGGCAAAGGGCAGGAAGAGGAAACAAUGAAAGGUUUGAGUAUGUAAAGUAUUUUUUAAGUCACUGAUGGAUGCAGUUUGCCAACGUUGUGUUAGGAUAUUUGCAGCUAUGUUUUUAAGGAAUAUUGACAUUUAAUUUUCAUUUCUCAUAUUGUGCCUAUGAGAAUUUGGUAUUAAGAUUUAGCUAACCUCAUAUCAUUUGUUUAGAAAUAUUUCUUUUCUCUUUUUCAUUUUUGCUGCCUAUUAUUGUUACAUAUAACAAAUAUAGAACAUUUAAUGAAGUUUAAAUGCUAUAGUAUAAAGUGCACACUAAUUUAAAAGCCUCCCAUGGCAAGAAAGAGAACUUUGUAAACCCCAUAACACCUUAUUUGCUCCUUUCUAAUCACAACCCCUAUCUUCAUUCCAGAAGUAACAACUAUCUGCAAUUCAAAUCACGUUAUUGUUUAACUUUGUAUAUUUUAAUUUGAAUAUGUAUCCCUAAGCACUAGCUUGGUUUUGCCUGGUUUUGGAUUGCACAUGAAUGGAAUAAUACUGUACACAAUAUUUUUGAAUUUAACUAUUUUUGAUCAAUAUUAUGUUUCUAAAAUUAAUCAUGUUGCAUAUAGAGAUAGAUCAUUUAUUCAAUUGCUGUAUAGUAUUAAUGGAAUGACAAUUCAAAAUUUAUCUAGUCUAGUGGAAACACAAAGUUGGUUUAUUUUGAGUUUGGAGACUAUGAUGAUGAUGAUGCUACGAACAUUCUUUAACAUGUAACUUAUUAUUGAGUACAUGAGCAUACAUUUCUAUGAUCUUGAUCUGGAACCAUUCCGUUGCCUAUUUCUUCUGGUCUUGUUUUGGCAGUUACGACUUUCUAGAUAUUUGUCAGUUUCAAUUAUUUAUGUUUUCAUGUAAUUUUGAUUAUAAUAUCAUCUUAUUAAAUUUUUAAUACCAACAGAAUAUAUCCUUUAAAUUCUUCAUAUUAUUUGCUUUUCUUUUCAUGAUUUAUCUUACCAGAAGUUUGCCUAUUUUGUUAGUCUAUUCAAGUCUGUCUUGGUCGAUCUUUUCAGAUGUAUUAUUUUUCAUUAAUUUCAUCUCUUAUAUUGUUAUUUAAUUAUUUUUACUUCCGUUGAGUAUGUUUGCUGUUAUAUUCCUGGCAUACGUUUUCCUCUUAGAAUUUUUCAGCAUUUCUCACAAGGUUUUACUAUAUUUUAUUAUACUUAAUUUUAAAUAUUUUCUAAAUUUAUUGUGAUUUUUCUUCCACCAUAGACUAUUUUUAAAAUAUAUGUUCGAGUUUCCAUUUACAUAAAAUUUUCUCUGCUAAAAUUUAUGUUAUGCAUAUAUGGUCAAUUUUGAUAAAUGUUUUGUGUUUGCUGAAAAUAAUGUGUAUCCUGUAGCUUUGGGGUGCAGUGUUUCAUACAUCCACUAGAUCUAUUUGUAAUCAUGUUAUUUAAAUCCUAUUUACCUUUUCUGAGUUUUGUCUUUUUAUUCUAUUAUUUCUUGAGAUUUAAUGUUAAACUAUCCUGCUAUGAGUAUAGGUUUAUCUAUGUCUUUUAGAAGUCCUGUCAACUUUUACUUUACAUAUUUUGAUGCCAUGCUGAUGAGUGCAUAGAGCGUUAGAAUUGUAGUAUCUUCAUGGCAAAUAUAACCUCUACUCACAUGAGGUGACAUUAUCUAUUCUAAUGUCUUUUUCCUUAAAAUCUAUUUAGCCUCACGCCUGAAAUCCCAGCACUUUGGGAGGCCGAGGCGGGUGGAUCAUGAGGUCAGGAGAUCGAGACCAGCAUGGCUAACACAUGGUGAAACCAAGUCUCUACUAAAACUACAAAAAAUUAGCCGGGCAUGGUGGCAGGCACCUGUAGUCCCAGCUACUCGGGAGGCAGAGGCAAGAGAAUGGCAGGAACCUGGGAGGUGGAGCUUGCAGUGAGCCAAGAUCACACCACUGCACUCCAGUGUGGGUGACAAAGCGAGACUCCGUCUCAAAAAAAAAAAAUCUAUUUAGUAUAUAUUAAAAUGAUUACAUUAGCUUAUUUUUGUUAGUGUUUUAUGGUGUGAUUUUUCUAAAUUUUACUUUUAACUUCUCUUUGUUAUUAGGAUUUAGAUAUAUAUCUUGUACAUAGCAUAGAGGUCGUAAAAUGGGACCUAGAGCUAUAUGCUAACAUUUUAUUCCUUGUAGGAUAAGAAAUGUAGUCUUGUAGGAGUCCCCUCUCCCCCUUGAAGUUGUAUAUUAUGUAAAUUUUUGGUCAAUAAAAUAUUGUGGAAAUGACAUGUUGCUUCAGAGUGAGAGCAUUUACUCACCACUAUAAGACUGCAAAUUUCUCAUCUUCUUGCCUUGACACUCAAACAAGGGUCAAUAAACCAUCUAUCAGCCUGGAUUCUUUUGUGACCACUAUGAGCACAGGACAUGUAACAGAAAUCAAAAACAAAAACAAACAACAAAAACUUCUCCUACGUGGAGUCCCUGAGCUUUGGGGAUCUUGUUAGUACAGCAUAGACUAAGCUAUCUUGGCAAGUAUGAGACUGGCCUCUUGAACUGGUAUGUUACUAAAACAAAACACCUAACUUAUGUGACACUGGCUUAAUACUUGAUUCAUUGGCAGUGAGUGGCAAGAAAAAACAUUACUGUUUACUGUAAAACAAGAUAGGGAGUGGCAAAACAUUCGAUAGCAGUCACCUGUGGUUAUGUGGGAGGUAAAUCACAUAUUUGAAAGUUUUGUAACUCUAGAAAAAAAAUAUAAUUGAAUAUAUUAAUGGUUCAUUUGACAAUUAAAAAAAUUGACUUUAGAAAAUAAUUGCCUACUGUCUAGCUAAAUAGCAAACAGAGGGAGAUGCUCUAAAAGAAAAUGAUAUUUAUUUGGGAGUAAUAUUGCAAUGAGAAUACAUGUGCCAUAGUAAAUUAUGUGUGUAUUCAGGGACAUUAGAAAAGACAAGGAUUUCUAAAAGAGGAAGAUUACAUAAUUGUUUUGAGAUAAUUAACCUUGGAUCCAAGGAUCAGGAACAAGGGUGACACCUGUCUAAGGUUAGACAAGGAGGUUCUGAGCAGAUGUCCUUGCAGAAGUAUCUUUUUGUGUAGGGUUGCAGUGGCCUUUGUGCAAUGUUGUUGUUUUGUAGAGUCUUUUCUGGUAGCUCUUGUUAUAAGUCGUAUUUACAUUAAGAACUCUCCCCUCAUGGCCUUCUCCAGCUCCAUUUGUCAGAGUUUUAACACAAGUGACUUCAUUUUGAUUCUGACAAUUUUAUACUACUUUGCAAGCAGGAAAAAAAUAUAUCAGAAAGAAGAGUCUAGAAACUUGAGAUUUUGCAGAGCUGGAAGAGGCAACUGCUUCUCAACACUGAAUAGUAUUUGAGUUUCUAAGCCUGGUUAAAACUCAGCCAUGGCUGGGCACGGUGGCUCACGCCUGUAAUCCCAGCACUUUGGGAGGCUAAGGCAGGUGCAUCACAAGGUCAGGAGAUCGAGACCACCCUGGCUAACACGGUGAAACCCCAUCUCUACUAUUAAUACAAACAAUUAGCCUGGCAUGGUGGCGGGCACCUGUAGUCCCAGCUACUUGGGAGGCUGAGGCAGGAGAAUGGUGUGAACCCAGGAGGCAGAGCUUGCAGUGAGCCAAGAUCAUGCCACUGCACUCCAGCCUGGGCCACAGAGUGAGACUCCGUCUCAAAAAAACAAAAAACAAACAAACAAAAAAACUCAGCCUUAAGACUAGGAUUAUCUCAAGGGUAUGGUUGUUACAUCCAUGUUAAAAAUUCUGACUAGAUUAUAUUUACAGAAAAAGGUUCAACUGACAGUUACUGCUCUUUCAGUUUGACAAGGUAAUAUCAAGGCAGAGUGAUUAAAUAUCUGGUUUCCUGAAUGAAGCCUUACAAUGCUCAAAGUAUCUGAUAUUAAAUCCAGAGAGAAAAGCAGAGGGGUGAAAAAGCAACAAAACACAGCAAAUAUAAGAAGCAGCAGACUAGACAAAAACUGUGACUUGUUUGCUUAACUUAAACUCAACCAAUCAAAGACAGCCAACAGGAUAGCCAAACAUUUGAUUGGUUAGCUAUAAAGUUACCUUAUUUCAUCUGUCCUGUCUUUGCUUUUCUUCUUUGUCUGUCCUAUAAAAGCAUCCCCAUCGCGUUCCCUCGGUAGAGCUCCGGAACCACCUCAGUUUGGAGCUUUCCAAUUUAUGAACCAUCAUUUGCAAAUAAACUUUUAAAAAACUUUAGUGUGCCUUAGUUGACCUUAUUAACACAUGUUGAGCUAAAACCCUGUAUUAGUCUGUUCUCAUGUUGCUAAUAAAGACAUACACAAGACUAAGUAAUUUAUAAAGGAAAGAGGUUUAAUGAACUCACAGUUCUACAUGGCUGAGGAGGCCUCACAAUCAUGGUGGAAGACAAAGAAAGAGGAAAGGGACAUCUUACGUGGCAGCAGACAAGAGAGAGUUUGCAAGGCAACUCCCCUUUAUAAAACCAUCAGAUCUCAUGAGAAUUACUUAUUCAUUAUCAUAAGAACAACAUGGGAAAGACCCGCCCACGAUUCAGUUGCCUCCCACUGAGUUCCUCCCCAUGACACAUGGGAAUUACUCGGGAGCCACAAUUCAAGAUGAGAUUUGGAUGGGGACACAGAAAAACCAUAUCAAACCCUGUUCCAGAGAUGCAGUUUAACAUAUUAUGAGACAAAUGGGAGCUCACAGACAAUAUGAGAAUCUCUUGAAGAUUACACUUUUUUUCCUAGUUCUAAAAUUACAUCUUUUUUAAUGAGACUUAUAUUCUUCCCCCAACUCAGAACAUUUCCUUGUCUUUAAGGGAGACCUGCCACAGAUAGAGAACCAUAGAAAAUAACAGUAACAACCACAUAAACUGUCAUGUUAGCUAUGAAAAGAGUUGGUGGAAGGAAUGGGCUCUCACCAAGACAGUGAAAAAUAGAGGUAGGUGGUAAACAAAUAUGCAAAAGGACCAUUCAGAAACCCAAGCAAACUAUCAUUCUCCCCAUUUUACUGGUGCUAUAAAUACCUGAAAAAAAGUGCCACAGAAAUGGAUUAGUGUUAUCAUCAACAAAUAUAUUUGAGCCGGGCACAGUGGCUCACACCUCUAAUCCCAGCAUUUUGGGAGGCCAAAAUGGGAAGAUAUCUUGAGCCCAGGAGUUUGAGACCAGCCUGAACAACAUAAAAAGACCACCUCUCUAUAAAAUAAGAUAAAAUAAAAUAAAAUAAAAUAAAAUAAAAAAAAUAGCUGGGCAUGGUGGUGCACAUCUGUAGUCCCAGCUACUUAGAAGGCUGAGAUGGAAGGAUUGCUUGAGCCCGGAAGGCCCAGGCUGCAGUGAGCCAUGCUUAUGCCACUGCCAGUCAGCCUGGGUGACAGUGAGACUCAUAUAUAUGUAUACAUUUAAAUAUAUGUAUACAUGGGUGAGACUCAUAUAUACAGAUAUGUAUAUAUUUGUACGUAUGAGAUAAGCUGGUGAGAAUGAGGUCAUUGAAGCAGAUAUCCUGUUCCUUGCCAAUUAAGUCAGUGAUGAAUUCCAUAGUUAAUACCACCAUGAAAAUGUCCUCCUCUAUACCUGGCUUCUCUUCAGAGAGAAAAAUUCCUAAUUUUAUAAUUUUUUUUAUUUUCAACUAAGGGAUUAAUACAAUAAUUAAGGGAUUAAAUAUUUAAUAUUUAUUGUUUCAGUACUUCUCUCUUGCUAUGUCCAUUAAUUCCAUUGCUCAUUGUUAAUUUGUUGUUAAUUACAUUAAAAUCAGUUCUUCUGUAGGAUCAUGUCAUAUUGAUCUUUAUGAAAUCAGAGCAAUCAUUUUUCAAAUGAUUCAGCUGGCAAUUUUCAUACUAACAAAUAUUUUAGUUUUUUAUAAGAGCCACAGGUGAUAACUUUCCAUAUUCAAAAGAAUACCCAGUGAAGUCUAGUGUUCUCAGAUGCAGUUACGGACAGUUUUCCUUUCACUGUUUUCACUUGUUGCUUCACCCUAAACUUCAAUUUAUGUACACAUUACAGUCCCCAAUUAGGAGACUAACAGGAUGUUGAAGAAUGGCAUUGGCAGGACAUUUCUGAAUUCAGUAGCAGGAAUGAACUCAAAACCAGCAGUACUGAGUCAGUUCUUGUUCUCUUCUGACUGAAUUCGUGUUCAUGGAAAUGUUUCUGCAAGACUGAGUGGUCACAGUGUCAGAAGGCUCCUCAGGUUUUGCCUCUUCACACAUGUCCAUUUCCCCUUUGACCUUCUGCCAUGUCAAGAUACAGCUGGAAAGCCCUCACCAGAAGCUGAGCAGAUAUCAGUGCCUGCUUUUGGAACUUCCCAGCCUGCAGAAACAUUAGGUCUUUAUAGAUUGUCCAGCUUCAAUAUUAUGCAGCCUUAAAAAGGAACAAGAUCAUGUCCUUUGCAGGGACAUGGAUGAAGCUGGAAGCCAUUAUCCUCAGCAAACUAAUGCAGGAACAGAAAACCAAACACCACGUGUUCUCGCUUAUAAUUGGGAGGUGAACAAUGAGAUCACAUGGACACAGGGAGGGGAACAACACUUAGCGGGCAUGUUGGGGCAGGACGGGGGUGGGAGAGCAUUAGAGAAAAGAGUUGAUGCAUGCUGGGCUUAAUAUCUAGGUGAUAGGUUGAUAGGUGCAGCAAACCACCAUGGCACACAUUAACCUAUGUAACAAACCUGCAUAUCCUGCACAUGUACCCCAGAACUUAAUAAAUAAAUAAAUAAUACAUUUUUAAAAGAUCCACAUGAUCAAAAAUGCAAAAAAAAAUAAAUUAUCCAACUUCAGGUAUUCUUUUAUAGCAACAUAAAAUGGACUAAGACAAAACUCUGUGGUGAAAUCUCCAAUUAUUUGUAAGAUGAAGUCGUAGAAAUGGGUGAAGUCCAAAAAGCAGGUUAUAAUCUAUAUAAACAUUUAAGACUUUUAUUAAUAUUGACAAAGUCCCCUACAAAAUGCAUGCACCAAUGUAAGCUCUCACUAGCAUUAAACGAGACUGCUCGUAACUUUGCACACAUUAUAAUUCUAUGUAACAAUUUACAAAAGCAAAAUGUGGCCAAUUUGAAAUGCAAAAUAGAGCACUUGUUAUUCAUUUUACCAUAGUACUAUACUAAACUUACGUUUUUGUUUAAAUGUGAGGCUGAAUUUUUUAUAUAUGAUAAUCUGGUUUUUAAAAUUAUUUUUAUCUUUUUUAUAAAACAGUAAAAGUAUUAAAUUUUUUUCUACUGUUUAUAUUGCAAAUAGACUUUAAAGUUUUUAAUCUAUUAUUUACCUUUCUAUAUUUAUUUUCUUGAGGCAUUCAGAAAUUCUUCCAGUCAUGCUAUUAAAUGCAUUCAUUUUAAAUGUACUCUGCCUUUAAUAUCAUGUUUAAACAUGUCUUCCCAACUUUCAAGAUUACAAAACAAUUCUUGGUAUUUUCUCUGUUUGAUUGUUUACUUUUUCAAUUCUAUAUUUAAUCCUCUUAUUUACUUUGGAAGAAGAAGUAUGUUACACAUUUGUCUUAUUUCAAAUUGCAAUAUUGUUGUUACAAUACUAAUUAUUGCAGGGUUAAUUUUUCUUCACAUAUUUAAGAUGGAAAAAUCUAUCUCACACAAUAUAUUUGUAAACAAAAAAAGAUAUUUAUAAACUCUAUAAUUUUUUUGUUGCACUGGAGUUUCCUCAUUCUUUCAUGAUGUUAUUCUAUGCCACUCUUUAAAGAGAAGUGUUGGAGGACAUGAAAGGUGAGAGGAUAGACAUGUAACUAUUUGUUGGACACCUAACUUAGGAUGGACAGAUUAUAUUAUUUUUAUCAGCAAAUGUGAACUCAUCAGUCUUUUCCUUAAUGACAUGUGCUUCCUCAAAUUAAAGGCAGUAGAGUCUUAUUUUGAUUUUCUUGUAAAAGUUUUAAAGAAUUGUUUUCAAAUCUAAAGUGAUAGUACAUCUAAUGUAGUUUUUCUGUUUGUUGUGAGUUAGAAAUACAAUUUUGUCCCAAUAUUAAAUGACAGAGGUCUCAAUAUCAUUAGUUGAACAGUCUACGUUUUUUUUUUGUUGAUUUCUAAUGCCAAAUCUAUCACGUACGGAGGUUCCUAUGUGAUAAGAAUAAACAAUCUGGUCUCACCAGACCUGUCUUUAGUUUGAUCUGCUGACCUAUUACUUAUUAUAUACAUUUUAUUUCUGUGUCACAACCUUCAUUGUUUUGAUUUUUUUAAUAAUUUUUUUGAGACACGGUCUUGCUCUGUCUCAAAAAAUAUUAAAAAAAUUUUUUUAAUCUUUUUUUUUUUUUUCCUGACAGAGUCUUGCUCUGUAGCCCAGGCUGGAGUGGCUCAAUUAAGGCUCACUUCAGCCUUGACCUCCUGGGCUCAAACAAUCCUCCUGUUUGAUUCUCUGUGUAGCUAAGACUACAGUUGCCACUAUACCCAGCUACUUUUUUGAUGCUUUUAGAGACAAGGUCUCACUGUGUUGCUCAAGUGGGUCUUGAAUGCCUUAACUCAAGUGAUCUUCCCAUCUCAGCCUCCCAACAUGCUGGGAUUACAAGUAUGAGCCACUAAAUAAAUAAUUUAAAUAAGUCUUGCUAUCUACUGGAUACCCCUACCUUAAUUUUCUUUUUCAAGAAUUGUCUGAAUUAUUUUUGAAUACUUAAUUCAUGUGUAAUUUAGGACUGUUUUGUCAAUUUGAAAAUAAAUUUCUUUAAGAUUCUGGUUAGAAUUAUAUUGAAUAUGUGAAUUAAUUUGAGCAUAAUCAAUGUCUUUGAAAAUUAAUUUUUGCAUAUCUAUAUAGUUCAAAUCCUUCACUAAAGUAUUAUAGUUAUGUAAUUUCACAAUAUAUAACAUCAUGAAACACUUUUCUGAGACUUAGUCAUAAUCAAAAUAUAGUUCUUAUUUGUAAUAAGAAAGGGAAUUUUUUUAAUUCCACAUUUUAAUGGACCAGUGCUGGUGAAUAGGUGUAAUUUUAGCCCAUAUAUAUUGAUAUUGUACUCAGCAAGCUUAUCAAAUUUGUGUUAUUUCAAAAGUUUUCCUGUUGAUUUUUAAAUUAUCUAGGUGGAAUUACUACUAUUAGUAUAUAAUUUCUUUAAAUUUCCAUCCAAAUUUCUAUGUAACAAUAUUUUUGUCAAAGUGUAUUAGUUAAAUGACCUAACGAAAUUGUCAAUAAACAAGUAUCUUUGUCUUAAUCUUGAUUAAAUGAAAAGCUCUAUGUUACACUAAUAACUAUGCUUCUGUAUUUGUUUAGUAGACAUACAAGUUAUUAAAUGUUGCUUCUAUUUAAACUUGGUUUGGGUAUUUAUCUUGAUUAGGAGUUAAAUUAGAUUAAACAUUUUUGCAACAUCUGUUGAGAUAAUUUUAUGUAAAUUAAAAUUAUUUACUUUCUAGUUUUAAAUUAUCUUCAAAUUCUUAGAAUGAAUCUUUUCAUUUGUAAUAUAUUUUAAGUAUAUAUUAUGAGACUAAUUUACUUUUACACUUUUUUUUAGCAGUUUUGUGCCUGUAUCUAAUUGCCUACCUUCUCAUUAUUUGCUGUCCUCUACUGUUUUUACUCACUUUGAGAAUAAUUUUUUAACUUCUUAAAAUAAAUGAGAAUAAAACAUUUAGGUUCACUGAAGUAGUUUGGAGAAGGUAAAAAUUAUGACAUUUUUAAACUUAGUAAAAGUUUUUUAUAAAUCCAUCUGAAUUUGAUAUCUUGUGUAUAUUUUGAUAGUCCAUUCAAAAUCUUUGAAAUUGUUGAUUUAUUAAAGUUUUUUACUACUAAUAUAAAUUUUUGUUAACCUAUGCUUUUUAAAAACUUGGCAAUUUCAACUGAGUUUUUAAAUUUUGGAAUAAAAUUAUUUAGAACUUUGAUUAUAUAAAGCUCUGCUAUUUAGUAUUUUCUACAUUUCAUCAAUUUUUCUGCUUCUCGUAUUUCUUGAUCAGUACCAUCAGACUUUUGAAUUUCCUAAUCUUUAAAAGAUUUUGGUUGUACUACCAUUGUCUAUUAUAUUUUGAUUUUCUAUUUAUUUAUUCAUUCAUUUAUUUAUUUACUACUUUGAUUUUGGUUGACAUCCAAAAGCAUAAUUACUGCCCUUCAGACAAAUUCUAACUUUUCCUUUUGCUGAGUCUAUGACUUGGGAAAUUUACUUAACCUUGCUAUCCCUUGGAUUUUUGUUUGUUUAGUUUUUGAGACAAGGUCUCACGCUGUCACCCGGGGCUGGAGUGCAGUGGUGCGAUCUUGGCUCACUGUAGUUUUGACCUCGCAGGCUCAAGUGAUCCUUCCACCUCAGCCUCCCUAGUAGCUGGGACUACAAAGGUGCACCACCAUACCCGGCUAAUUUUUGUAUUGUUUGUAGAGGGCAGUGGGGUCUCACCAUAUUGCCCAGGCUUGUCUCGAACUCCUGAACUCAAGCAUCCACCUGUCUUGACCUCCCAAUGUUCGGGGAUUACAGGCAGGUGCCACAGCACCCUGUCAUGCCUCUGAUUCUUUAAAAACCAAAGGGAAUGAGACUGUUUUUAGGAAUAAAUAUAAAAUAAAUAGCACACCUAAACCACCUAGAACAGUACCAUGUACUAAGUAAGCGCAAGGUACAUAUUAGCUCCUUCUUAACUUAUUCACCCUUCUUUAAAUUUUUCUGUUGUUCAUUUUUCUUAACUGAAGGUGAAUAUGUGCCUCAUUCAUCUGGAAAACUUUUUUAUAAAACAUGUACUAAUGGAUAUGGAUUCUUAGCUUUAGCCGGUUUUUUCAUUUUGAUUGUGAAAAGCUUUUUCGUUGCUGAGUUCUAAACAUUUAUCUUUUAUGUAGAAAUGUUCAUCUUUUUCUCAGUUAUAGAGAAUAGUUCAAUUUUCAAACUUUUUUGAUUGAUUUAACAUUUUACUACUUUACAUUCUACGUAAUACUUAUUCCAUGGAAUCUGUUCUUUGUUAUAGUGUACAUGGUUUAGGUGUGUAAAUGUUUCAUGUGUAUUUGAAUGUUUGUGUCCAGAUUUCUGUCAAGUACAGAUUUCUACAUAAAAGUAUUGAAUUAAUUUUUGCUAAUUGCAUUCUUAAAAUAUUCCAUAUCAUUCUUUCUUCUGCUUGAUAUGGCAGUUUAUUAAGUGUGUCUUACAUUCUUAUUAUUUGUGGAUUCUUCAGUUUCUGUUUGUGAGGCUUCUGCUUUAUCUAUUUACGUAAUGCAUUGUUAGGUAUGUCCAAAUUCAUGAUUAUUGCAUCUUUUCCAUGAAUUUUUUCUUUUUCUUUUUUUUGAGACGGAGUCUCGCUCUGUCGCCCAGGCCGGACUGCGGACUGCAGUGGCGCAAUCUCGGCUCACUGCAAGCUCCGCUUCCCGGGUUCACGCCAUUCUCCUGCCUCAGCCUCCCGAGUAGCUGGGACUACAGGCGCCCGCCACCGCGCCCGGCUAAUUUUUUGUAUUUUUAGUAGAAACGGGGUUUCACCUUGUUAGCCAGGAUGGUCUCGAUCUCCUGACCUCAUGAUCCACCCGCCUCGGCCUCCCAAAGUGCUGGGAUUACAGGCGUGAGCCACCGCGCCCGGCCCUUUUUUUUUUUUUUGAGACAGAGUUUUGCUCUUGUUGCCCAGGCUGGAGUUCAAUGGUGUGAUCUUGGCUCAGUGCCACCUCUGCCUCCCAGGUUCAAGUAAUUCUCCUUCCUCAGUCUCCUGAGUAGCUGGGAUUACAGGCACACGCCACCAUGCACAGCUAAUUUUUUUGUAUUUUUAGUAGAGAUGGGGGUUUCACCACAUUGGCCAGGCUGGUCUUGAACUCCUGACCUCAGGUGAUCUGCCCGCCUUGGCCUCCCAAAGUGCUGGAAUUACAGGCGUGAGCCAACAUGCCCAGCCUUCGAUGAAUUGUUUUAUUCUUACUACUCUGUAAUCACCUGUCUUUAACUGUUACUGUUGUUUACUUUAAAUGUUAUGUGAUUAUUAGUUAUAAUUCAGUUAAAUAUGACAAAUAUAAACAAGCAAUUGAAUAUAUGCAUGUGGAAGAGCAUCUAUCUUUCACAUAACUAAAAAAUACAUAGGAAAGUUUUUGUGGCACAAAUUGUCCAAGGGAAUAGUGUGAUUCUAUCACCAACAAAUGAUAGGAUAAUAGACAUUAGGCAUAAGUAGCAGUUACUGUGCUCAUUAGUUAGUGGUAGAUUCUACCCAUUUAUUUUCUGUCACUGUGGUUUUCUGCUUUAGGUAUGCCUCUUGAAAGCAGAACAUAGUCGUGUUUUGUUUUCUUAUUUAUUCUCUGUCUUUUGAUAGAUCAAGCAAAUUUAUUUAAAUUCAUGAACAUUUCUGAUAACAUUGAACUUGCUUUUACUGUCUUAUUAAAAUUUUGCUAGUUAUCACUCUCUUUUCACUCUUUUUUUGCUUUGAGAUUAAAGUGAUAAGUUCUUUUUAUUCAUUUCUCCAUCUGUUUUUUUUUUUUUUUUUUUUUUUGAGACGGAGUCUCGCUCUGUCGCCCAGGCUGGAGUGCGAUCUCAGCUCACGGCAAGCUCCGCCUCCUGGGUUCACGCCAUUCUCCUGCCUCAGCCUCCCGAGUAGCUGGGACUACAGGCGCCUGCCACCACGCCCAGCUAAUUUUUUGUAUUUUUAAUAGAGACGGGGUUUCACCGUGUUAGCCAGGAUGGUCUCCAUCUCCUGACCUCAUGAUCCACCCGCCUCGGCCUCCCAAAGUGCUGGGAUUACAGGCGUGAGACACGGAGCCCAGCCUCAUUUCUCCAUCUAUUCUAAGUUUCUAUUUUUAUAUAACAAAUCAUUCCCCAAAUUGCAGGCUUAAAACAGCAGUUUAUUACUUUUUUCCUCACGAUUCUGUGAAUUGCCUGGACUUAGUGGAUAGUCUCUCAUUGUGGUAUUUCAUGUAGUUGCCAUCAGAUAAGGGAUGGGACCACAGUCAUCUGAAGGCUCAAAUGGGAUGAACAUCUACAAUGAUCCAACUCAAUGGCUGACAUAGGGAGGAUUCCCUCUUUUUCUACUGAUUGGAAUAGUUUCAGAAGGAAUGGUACCAGCUCCUCCUUGUAACUCUGGUAGAAUUCGGCUGUGAUUCCGUCUGGUCCUGGACUUUUUUUGGUUGGUAGGCUAUUAAUUAUUGCCUCAAUUUCAGAGCCUGUUAGUGGUAUACUCAGGGAUUCAAAUUCUUCCUGGUUUAGUCUUGGGAGGGUGUAUGUGUCGAGGAAUGUAUCCAUUUCUUCUAGAUUUUCUAGUUUAUUUGCAUAGAGGUGUUUAUAGUUUUCUCUGAUGGUAGUUUGUAUUUCUGUGGAAUCAGUGGUGAUAUCCCCUUUAUCAUUUUUUGGGGGGUCUAUUUGAUUUUUCUCUCUUUUCUUCUUUAUUAGUCUUGCUACUGGUCUAUCAAUUUUGUUGAUCUUUUCAAAAAAACCAACUCCUGGAUUCAUGGAUUUCUUGAAGGGUGUUUUGUGUCUCUAUCUCCUUCAAUUCUGCUCUGAUCUUAGUUGUUUCUUGCUGUCUGCUAGCUUUUGAAUGUGUUGGAGAGCAGUUUCUCAUAAAAGCUUGUGGAUUCAACUGUAAAAGUGGCAAUCCACUCUGACUCCCCUCUCCACUGCAGAGAGCUUUCUUCUUUCACUUAUUAAACUUUUGCUCCAACCUCACCCUUUUGUGUCCACACUCCUUAAUUUUCUUGGUCAUGAGACCAUGAGCUCAGAUAACACCUUAGUAAUAAUAUCAAUGACCCGGACCUGUUUUGGUAACACCAGCUCUGGGGCCAGGACACAGGGGCACUCUCAGGCAGAAGACUGAAAUCUGUGCAAGUGGUAUACAAAUUUAUCCCUUCAUACACAAAUCUCAGGCCAGUCUCUCUCUUGGACUUCUAAAAUUUUACAUUCAUUGUGAUGAGAAUCAACAUUUUUGGUUCAUUUCAAAGGACAGGCUCAAGUUUUGCCAAUGCUAAUAUGGCUCAGCAGAAAAAUGCAUGUGGCUUGUAUUAAGAAAGCACAUAAAGGAUCUACAUUGACUGGGUUUUCAUAAUCACAAAAAACGAAUAAAUUUGUAUGAGUAUCUUUAUAUGAAGGCAAGGAGGAAAACAGGUGAAUGGAAGCCUACGUAAAUGUGCUUAUGAUUUAAAACAAACUUAUUUCCUCAGGAAAAAUAUAUUUUUCACCUCACCUGUUAAAGUCUUAGGAAAGCUUAACCUUGAUAAUCUCCUAAUAACAGAACUUAUGUUUCUUUUCUGAACCUCAUUCCUUCUCAUAUUGUAAUAAUGAAAUGAAUAAAUGAAUAGCAAGUGAGUAGUGGUGCACACUAAACUCUGAGUACUGACUGCCUUCUAUUCCACUUAAUACCUUUAUAAGAACAUUGUUAUGUACCUAAGUCAUGUCAUCUAUAAAACUAAGGUAAUGAUAACAAUCAUAUGUCCCUAAUAUAAUGGUUUUGAUGAUUAAGUGGAACAUAGUAAAUGUUUAAAAAUGUUUUCUAUUAUAACCAAUUUGGCUAGGAUAGGUGGAAAGAAUAGAAAUAUGAUAAUUAAUUGUGAAAUGUAUAAUAUAUAUUAAUAGGUCAUCAACAUCAAAUUAAAAAAUAUAGAUGAUUACCAUGAUAGUGAAACCAAAGUUUUUAGACAAGUCAAAGCAAAGUUGAAGUCUCAGAGACCAUUGUGUUUAUUUGCUAACUGUAUUAUCAGACUGCUUAGUUGAUACAGUGAAUACAAUAAUUCUUCCAAUGUACAUAAACUGCCAGACAAGCAACUCAAUGCAAUUCACUCACUCUCGGAGAAGUUUAUCCCCUCUGCCAAUGUUCAUCUUUCCUGGCAAACCAUCCUUCAGUAUUCCAGGCAAACUAGAGCAAGGUGAAGUUGAAGAAGAUCCUACUUUAUAUUCCAUUCAGAGAGCUUCCGGGUCUUCAAAAAAGAUUUAGUCAUGUGGGUGUGAAAGAGCUGAGUCAUGAAAUUUGGACCUUAUUGUAAGUCCAGAAGGAAAAACAAGGGGUUUGAAGCACAAGGGUGAUAUGAUCUAAUUUCUACUUUUAAAUGAUCACUCUGAUUGUCGUGAGGGAACUGAUAUGGGAUGUACUGGGGGAAGAAUGUUACCAGGACCAGGUCGAGGCUGUUAAAGACCUCCAGGAGAGAGCAUUGUGGGCCGAACAACAAGCUUCUAGUAAAGAUCAUGCAAGUGGACACAUUUGAGAUGUAUUUUGAAGGUGGAAGAAAUUAGAUAAGCUAAUGGGUAGUGCCUGGAGGGAGUGAGGAUUUUUGAACCACUAGGUAAACACCUGUGAGUAACAGAGAAAAAGUUGGGAUGUGUUAUGAAAGAUGAAUCCUAAAAUUUCAUAUGUUGAAGACUGAUGCUUCAGGACCUCAGAAUGUGAACAUCCAUAGUAGAAGGGAAUUGUGUUGUUGACGGCUGCCACCCACUCUAGGUGCCCAAGCUCCUGCAGCAGUCCUACUUCUCCCUUUCACCCACACUCACUCCCAGACAGUGUCCCUUUCAGCUCUUCCAUCACCCCUUCUUUUGAUUUGGCUGGUGAGAGCAUAGCUGGUAUUUAUACUUUCUUGAUAUGCUAGUCUCUUUUGCUGAUUGUUGACAUUGGAGAAGGUCAUGGAAGGGACCUGAGCUGAGCGACCUUUAGGAGCAUUUCCUGUUCUUUUCCUGUACUCUGCUGCCAAGGAGAAAUCUGUCUUUCACCAGGCUUGCAGCUUUCUCCGUUACCCACAUCAUCAGGCAAUAUCUGUCUGGCACCCCUCUUUGUUCCCUUUCUCUGGCCUUCCUUUUUGACAUGAUGGUUGACCUGAAAUCACCAAGGCAGGACUGCUCAUCUCCAGGUCUAAUGGAAAACAGUAUCUGGUGAAACCAAAGAAAAUAAUCCCAGUAACCCACUGGGAGCUGCUUGGCUUAAGCACCUACCCUGUGCCUAAGAUACAACCCAUCAAGCCCAGCUAAAACUGAUCCAGUUUCCACAGGGCCAGAGAAGAAUUGCCAAUUAAGAAUGCAUUCCCACUUCAAAUAUGUCUAUAUUUAUUUCAGGGAAAAUAUCAGUCUGCCUGGGUCCCUUAUGAGAACAUUGUUGUCUGUAGAAAAAUCUAAUCUAUUAGGAAGCCUUCUUGUUUUGUUAUCUGCAACUCUUCAGAAGGGCCAGACCAGACCCUCGUAUGCACAGUACAGGAUCCACCCAUGCACAUCUGUCUAGGGCCUUGUCUUUAUGAUUUUCUGUCACAUGGCCUCUCAGCCAUGCCUCCAACCAAGCUAUCCUCAAAUAAACACUAGCCGUGCACAAAAAGUGAAAAAUUACACAAGGCCUACACAAGGUCUGAAAUGGAAAGUGCAGCUGGUGAUACCGAGUAGUAUAUUUUAUGAAUUGAGGAACAGGGAAUUUCUAGGUAUCACAGAGCAAUCAGCAGCUGAGAAGAGGAGUACCAAUCCAGGACCCUGGAAGGAUUUUUCAGAAACUUAAUAGUUUAUUGUCCAAUUGUAGAGACAAAAAUGAAAAUAAAGAUAGUGAGGAGUACCAUACACCAUUGCUUAGAAGAUUAAAUAAAUGUCAUCUCCCACAAGUCAUGUGGGGAGAAAAAAACUAUAUAGGAAGAAAAUUACAAACGACAAGGUAGUCUCAGCAUAUAAAAUAUCAACAAAUGAAUGUAAGAAAGAGAAUGAGAAAGAAUUAGUAUUAGAAUAUCAUAGAAAAAAUCAUCUUUGUGAAAGAAAACUCUGAUGAAACUGGUGACAUAAAUACUGAGUAAAAAACAGAAGACCAAUCAAGGCAUUUGAGGCUUGAACAGGCAUUACAAAUCAUCAAGUUGAAUAUAUAAGUAUGGCCACUUAGUUAUUAGUGGUGAAGACUACGGUAUUUGUUAGAAGAAAUAAAGUAGAUGAUGAAUUCUAUAGAAUAUUCUGGAGAAAGUGGAGGUCUUAGCUACAUGACAUCGUGUGGCUCACUUUGGGAACCAUGUUUCAGUUUGUUUAGGUCUAGAAAUUCCUUGGUGGUUUCUGUGUUCAGUUUUGCUUUAAUAAUCCCUAAAGAUAUUUUUUAAAAUACAAAUUUUUUAGCUUUCCUGUAUUGUACAGCACCAACGCUUGCCUGAGUGUAGUGAGAUUCACAGAGUUUGGAAAUUUCCUGUAGCAUGAGGAGGCUGCGGGGCAGCCUUCUGUCAUCUAUGUGUACCCAGCAGUGUGCUGUCCUCACACAACUCACGGAUAAGCAGAAAGCAUCUCUAUUACAUGAAAAAUUUAGCUAAAUAUACAAAUAUCCAUGCACACACAUCAUGAGAGAUGGAAAUAGGCUAUCAAAAGAGUCAGACAUAUUGACCGUCUUCACUGUUAGCUGUAGGAUUGCUGCCCAACCCCCUGACACACCCACACAAACUCACAUACACACAAAUGAAAAGCACAGUGGAAAGCAGAAUAGCAGUCUUUCCAAACAGAUUGAAAAACAAAUGAUGUCUAAAGUUCAAUCCUGACACUGUGCUGAUUGCUUGGACACAGUUCCGUCAAAACAUUUGUCCAAGUCAUAGUUGUACCUUUUAGAAAUUAGCCACAAACAACAUCCUCCCCAACCCUUCCUGCUAGGCUAGAGUCCCAGAAGAAAUGAGGGAUACACUUGACCUGAAGUAAGCAAAGCAGAACCCAGUCUCUGAGGCGAGGAGGCCCACCUGGUAGGGAGCUCAAAUGCGCCAUUGUCCUGCUUGUCUUUAUAAAGGGAGCUGACACGUUUCUCCCAGCAUAAAGUUGGGAGUGACACCAGAGCCUUCUGCAAGAUGCUUCUGAUUCUGCUGUCAGUGGCCCUGCUGGCCUUCAGCUCAGCUCAGGACUUAGAUGAAGAUGUCAGCCAAGAAGACGUUCCCUUGGUAAUAUCAGAUGGAGGAGACUCUGAGCAGUUCAUAGAUGAGGAGCGUCAGGGACCACCUUUGGGAGGACAGCAAUCUCAACCCUCUGCUGGUGAUGGGAACCAGAAUGAUGGCCCUCAGCAGGGACCACCCCAACAAGGAGGCCAGCAGCAACAAGGUCCACCACCUCCUCAGGGAAAGCCACAAGGACCACCCCAACAGGGAGGCCAUCCCCCUCCUCCUCAAGGAAGGCCACAAGGACCACCCCAACAGGGAGGCCAUCCCCGUCCUCCUCGAGGAAGGCCACAAGGACCACCCCAACAGGGAGGCCAUCAGCAAGGUCCUCCCCCACCUCCUCCUGGAAAGCCCCAGGGACCACCUCCCCAAGGGGGCCGCCCACAAGGACCUCCACAGGGGCAGUCUCCUCAGUAAUCUAGGAUUCAAUGAUAGGAAGUGAAUAAGAAGAUGACAGUGUUUCAAAUGCCUUGAAACAUAAUGUGAUCAUGCUCUAACUUCAAUAUACCAAUAAAAUAAUCAGCUUGCAAUUUCUGAUUAUAGCAUCUCCUUCUGAGUGUUUGGGACUCUGGAAUCUGAGACCCAUGUUCACAUUGUAAGAACAUCCAGGACCCCUUCUCCUUGAUGUUUCCAGCAAGCUUCUUUCCUCCUUAUCCUUAUUAAGUCAUCUGCCUGGGGAAGGAGUUCCACUGUUUCUUUCCUUCUCUGUCUUCUUAGCUCGAAUUUAAAUUGCACAAUUAUUUUCAGGUCAUUUCCUGAUAGUCUAGUCAGCUUAUGAAUGUAAGCAAAACAGGACCAAUGAAAGAAAGUCCCAGAAGCUGAGAGAAACUUUAACAAGUUUGAGAGUAACUUAUUUUGUUUUCUAGGAAAGUGAGUAUGGUUCUAUGCCUGUAUUCCCCAGAAGCCACUAGACCUAUUUUCCCCUAUUUUAUCACUGAUCAGUUCUGUCCCUGCCUAUGAUUCUUACCAUUCUUAAGAAAACCUGAAUGGAUUUCAUCAAGGCGGCAGCAUAAUUUGAAGGGCAAUUGCGUGUGAAAAUUGAUGUGACUUGAUUUACACAAUAGUCAGAAAACAUUUUAGAAAUUGAUGACUUUAUAAUGCAACCAGGAGUAUUGAAAAAAAAGUAAGCAAUGAGCUCAAAUAAUUAAAAAAGAGAGACAAAAUACACUUGGGAGAACAGAAAUAAGAAUUAAUGAAAAUUUAAAAGAUUAAAUGAAUGAGAAGAAAUGAUUCAUAAAUUUUGAACUAACAGUAAUAACUUCUUGAAAAUCCAAUAAAAUUGGCAAAAGAUUGUGAAAAUUCUGGAAGAAUAAGGGAAACAGAUAAUCUUCAGAGUAAUCAGGUAAAGCUUAAACAAGUGUUUUAAAAGAUGAGUUUUUCCUACAUUCUGAAAAGCAAACAUGAAAAACUGAACACAGUUUUUACAGAUAUACAAUAUGGAGUGACUUAUAUACAAAAUGACCUUAAAAAUAUAUUAAACUCAUUAUAGUAGUUAAUAUCUAAGUAAAAUAUGAUGAAAUUUAAUAGAGAAUUCACUCCUCCCAAAAGCACCUUCAUGGAAGAUUCCUCAUUAACAGGCAGUCCUUUAGUAUGCUGAUUUAUACAAAAUGCUGAAAAGAAGAGAAAUACCCCAAGUUCUUGAAAAAAAAUUUUUUGAUAUGACUACUCUAACAGUAAUAACUAUAAAUCUCACUUUAAAUAAUUUAAAACAAAUUAAAGUGAUAUAUGAGUUAAAUGACCAAGCAGACUUGAUUCCAGGAAUGUUAAGGAAUGUUCAUUAUUUGUUUUGGAUAAUGAAGUCAGCAGAGGAAAAAAAAAUAUGACCAUCUCAAAAGAUGCCAACGUUGUCUUUGAUAAUAUUUAAUAUAUUUUUUAAAAAACAAUUCUUGUAAAAUACUUUUUUGAUUAGCCUUCUGACCAUGAUUAAAAUGGUGUACCUCAAAGUAGCUGCUAACCUUAUGUGUAUCUGCAACACCCUGAAAAAUUAUCUAAUAAAAAGGCACAAAGAAAAAGCUUGUCAAUGUUGUGGAUAAUUAGAAAGUGAAUAAUUUUAUUUAAUAUUAGAUAAACAAGCACAUAACAGAGAUACAUAUAUUCAAAUGGAAGGAGUAAAAUUACCACCACAUGCAGAUCUGUUUUUCUGUCCAGAAAAUAACAAGAGAUUCUACUCAGGUAAAAAAGGAAAGGAAGGAAAACCAUUGUAAUUAAAAUAAAAUUUAAUACAAUAGCCGUUUAUUAAUUCAACUUCUAAAGAAUCUUUGUGAUUACACAAUGACCAGCUAGUAAAUAUAAUAAGAAAAUGAUUAUUCACAAAGGAACCAAAAGGCCUAGUCUUCGAAUUUUUAAUGCCAUUGUGAUAGCAAGCAUCUGAUUAUUUUACUCUAAGUUAUUUCCACUUCUGAUUUUAAGAACAGCUUCUUUCCCAGGGAUGGGUUCCCCCUAGUGAUGUAUUCUCUUCACCACAAGAGUUUGCAGCUCUGGCUUUCUUUCUGCUCAUCUGUAAAGAUAACUACAGCUCCUCUAUAAACCAUCUCACCAUUAUUACCGAAAUCAGACAAAUUCUGGAGAUAGUCAAAGCUGUGAGGAUUCGAAGAUCUCUUUCACAUCUUGACCCAGUCAAUUCCGUUCACCAGUGUUAUGAAUCCAUUCCCCAAAAUUCCAAUUAGGAAUUAUAUAUUUAUUAUUAUAAUGAGGAUACUAUACAAGGCAUUUAGCAUGGCUGCAAAGAGAGAGCUCCAAUGUCUAAAUGCAACGCUGACAAUUUCUUCAUCUAUCACAUGUACCUGUUAUACAUACUUAUUAAUUGGAUGUGCAGUUAAUUUCUUCCUUUAAAAAAAAAACUAUAGGCUCAAUAUGAAAGUAGAAAGCACUAAGGUGUACUAAUGAAUGGGCACAUAGCUUUUUUCACAAAAAGAUUAUUUUGCCCCAGACAGCUAUCUGCAUUCUGAUCCAGAUACUGUAUGUUCUUAACAUAAAGUGAAAUUUCUCAUACUUCAUGAUGAAAGAAAAAACUGAAUUCUCAUUGUUAAUAAACAAAUAAAGACAAUUCUCUGCA